CGCCCGGGGGCAGGGAGCCCGCGCCCAGAUCCCUCGGUUGGGGUCGCAGGUUUGUGAGACUGCGAGGAACACGUUCUCUGUCCCACACCGCUGAGGCCUGCACAGGUGGGAGGCGCUGGUCUGCCAGAGGCGCCCUUGGCACCAGGGAGGGGCUUCCUGGACCUUAGAUCCCAGAUUUGAGGCCCCCAUCCCACUCGCUGUUUCUGUCCUUUGCGCCUGCUCCUCUCUCUGACUCCUGCCCUGGGUUCUGGUUCUGCUCCAUCUCUGCCCUCACUUGCCACUCCCCUGUAGCUCCUGGCUGGGCACACACUCCUUCCCAUCCUCCGCAGUCGUUGGGGGAGCCAGAUACAGACCUCCAGGCCAGGGGUGUAUGGAGAUGACAGCUGGGGGCUCAGAGUGGUCCCUCUUGCCCCAUAGCUCUUCAGCCCUUCAGCUCUGACCUAGCUUCUUGGCUGGGGUCCUGGGGGGUGGGGGUGGGAGGCUCUGCUACUCACUUCAGCCUGGCCCUCAUGCCUGCCUGGCCAGGAGAGGGAGGUGCCCGCCUCCUCUCUCCCCUAUCCCUGGCCCGCCAUCUUGAGACCUGUGGCACCCAGUGCCCCACCCGGCCCCAGCACCCAGGGGAGUGGUCUCCAAGGUGAUGAUGCACCCAGGGCCAGUUGCAUUCCUUUCUCCCCACCAAGCCCAGGAUGCUCAUGUUCGUGCUGAACCAGCAGGACAUGUGUCCCCAGGGGCUUGCCUUCCGCCACAAAGGCUCUUACAAUCCAUGAACUCCCUAGGAGCUGAGCUCCUGCCCUCCCUGUUCCCUGGGUCACCCUCAUUGCCUCAGGACCAGUACCUGGGACCCUAUUCUUUCCCCAUCUGAAAAAAUCCCCUGGUCUUCCCAGGUCCUGGAGCCCCCUCAACCUCCAGGGCACCCCCAUCCCAGCCCCCACCCCCUAGCCUUCAUCAGCAUGCAGGCUCAGGCUGCCCAAACACAAGGGGAUUGUUCUUCUUGCAUGCUCAGGGUGGGGGGCUGGGAGCAGGCAGCCCACACACCCUGGCAGGCCCAGGCCACGAGGAGGCUGGCUUGCCCCACCCUGUGUCCCCAGACAGGCUGUCCACCCUCCCUACUCCCAUCACUGCUGCCCCUCCAGCCUCCAUCACCAUUGCCCAGUGGCGCUGACAUCUUGAGGAAAGAGCUCUGAGCUGCACAGGUAGACCCCUGGGUUCUCCAGCUCUGCCAGUUGUCUCCCAUGUAGCCUUACAAACAUUUCCCUUCCUCUCUGGGCCGCGAGCCCCUCUUGUGAUUGGUAAGACCUUUCCAGCUGUGACAGGCUGAGCCCAACUCGACUCUGUGAAACGUACCCCACCCCCCAGCCCUUCUUCCAGUCCCCCUCUUCCAUGAGGAGACCCACUCUGCUCCCACCCUCUGAAAACCUAAAGCACAGCCCAAAUCCCCCACCCCAGCAGCAUACCUAGGGAGCUCCUAGUCCUGGUAAAACGGCAGGAGUAGGGCUGGGGAUGCUGAGAAAGGAACCAGGAAUCCUGUCCAGGCAGGUCCUACCUCUGCCCAUGUGGCUGGCCCUCAUGUCUGGGUCUUCUCACUCUACUCUCAUUACUCCUCCGGGACCCUCAGCCCCAUCUUUGGUUCCAAAUGUCCCCAGGCCCCAUGAACCUUAACUCUUCUCCCUGCACACUGACCCUGGUCUUGUCUCAAAUUUCCUCUUUCUGGAGCUCUGUGUAUAGUGGAAAGACAGGCUCAGAAAUGCCCAGCGGGGACUUCUUUGAGUUGCAGCAACAUCUUUGAGGGGCACAGAGGCCUGAGUGAUCACAUCUGACUUGGAAGCCUGCGGAGGGCUUCACAGAGGAGGUGGCGUUUGAGAAGGAUUUUGACAGAGAGUGGGGAGGAUGGGCGUUUUGAGCUGAGCCUCUGGAGUCCCUGUGGCAGAACUCAAAUGGAAGGAGGAGCAGCUGCACCCAGGGGAGCAGGGUGUCACCUCCGUUGGAUAGGCCAUUUCCAGCACAUAGAAGAGAGAUUGGAAACCAACGUGCAGAACUGCCAGUCCCCUGACACGCUGUGCCCCACCCACUGCAGCCCAGUGCUGAAUGAACCCUGCCCAGAGGUGUCUGUAGUGAGCUUCUGCCCUAGUGACUUUUGGUAGGUGGGAGUGUGCCUCAAUUCCCCCCUCAACCCCUGCCUCAAGCCUUUACCAGGCAGUGGCAAGACCUGACCACACCCGAGGCCUCCCUGCCUUCAAGGCUUCCCAUGGCUGCUCCAGCUUCCUCCCCAGCUGCUCUUCUGUGCUCCAUCCACCAUCUGGCUGCUGGACGAAAGUGCCUCUCAUAUGGAAGCCGGCCAGGUUGCAGCGCGGACACACUCGCAGGUCGCUGUGGCCCCAGCCUCGCCUGACAGAAUGAGCGGCUCGGACGGGGGACUGGAGGAGGAGCCAGAGCUCAGCAUCACCCUCACGCUGCGGAUGCUGAUGCACGGGAAGGAAGUGGGCAGCAUCAUCGGGAAGAAGGGCGAGACUGUAAAGCGAAUCCGGGAGCAGAGCAGUGCCCGGAUCACCAUCUCCGAGGGCUCCUGCCCUGAACGCAUCACCACCAUCACCGGGUCUACAGCAGCUGUCUUCCAUGCAGUCUCCAUGAUUGCUUUCAAACUGGAUGAGGACCUUUGUGCUGCUCCUGCAAAUGGUGGAAAUGUCUCCAGGCCUCCAGUGACCCUGCGCCUUGUCAUCCCUGCCAGUCAGUGUGGCUCACUGAUUGGGAAGGCUGGCACCAAGAUCAAGGAGAUCCGAGAGACUACGGGUGCCCAGGUACAGGUGGCAGGGGACCUGCUCCCCAACUCCACAGAGCGAGCUGUUACGGUAUCUGGGGUGCCUGAUGCCAUCAUCCUGUGUGUGCGCCAGAUCUGCGCUGUUAUCCUGGAGUCCCCACCCAAAGGAGCCACUAUCCCCUACCAUCCGAGCCUCUCCCUAGGUACUGUUCUUCUCUCUGCCAACCAGGGCUUCUCUGUCCAGGGUCAGUAUGGGGCUGUGACCCCAGCUGAGGUCACCAAGCUCCAGCAGCUCUCAAGCCAUGCGGUCCCCUUUGCCACACCCAGCGUGGUGCCAGGACUGGAUCCCGGCACACAGACCAGCUCACAGGAGUUCUUGGUUCCCAACGAUUUGAUUGGCUGUGUGAUCGGGCGCCAGGGCAGCAAGAUCAGCGAGAUCCGGCAGAUGUCAGGGGCACAUAUCAAGAUCGGGAACCAAGCAGAGGGCGCUGGGGAGCGGCAUGUCACCAUCACUGGCUCUCCGGUCUCCAUCGCCCUGGCCCAGUACCUCAUCACUGCCUGUCUAGAGACGGCCAAGUCUACCUCUGGGGGGACGCCCAGCUCGGCCCCCGCAGACCUGCCUGCCCCCUUCUCGCCACCCCUGACGGCCCUGCCCACAGCUCCCCCUGGCCUGCUGGGCACACCCUAUGCCAUCUCCCUCUCCAACUUCAUCGGCCUCAAGCCCAUGCCCUUCUUGGCUUUACCACCUGCUUCCCCAGGGCCGCCGCCGGGCUUGGCGGCCUACACUGCCAAGAUGGCAGCAGCUAAUGGGAGCAAGAAGGCUGAGCGGCAGAAAUUCUCCCCCUACUGAGGCCAGCUGAGGUACAGGCAGGGGCAGGCAGGACCACCAGCAGGGGGCUGCCUCUGCACCCUACCCGCCCAAGGAGACUCCACCCUGGGGUCCCAAACGCCGCUAACGCCCAGACGCAUGGAUGCACCCCCUACCCUGCCUCCAUCUAUGGGAGUUCUUUCUCUCAGAGUGGGGGCAGUUUCUGGCCCAGGGGUCUGAGCUGCGGCAGCCCCAGGGCAGGGGGCCCUACCUCCUCAGCUCUGUGCUUGGAUACAGGGAGCAGCCAGGAGACUCCCUAGUGCCCCCACCAUGGCGGGUGUCACUCACGCACUCCCCAUCCCUUAGGGCUUCCUGGCCUACUGCAUCCUUGUGGGAGUCAGGGAGGAGGGCCCGUUGGGUAGCUGGGGCCAGGCUUCUCUCCCCACCACCUGCAGAUUUCUUGCUGCUUCCACUGAUACCCUUUUGACUGGAAUGAACUGGCUGGGCUUGUCAGGGGGCACCCCAAAGAGGGGGCACUGCCAGGUAGCUGGGGGAGUGGCAUGGGGCAGGGGCCCAGUUCUCAGCAGCAGACACUCUGUACAGUUUUUUCAAUCCCUGUUUUUGAAUAAAUAUUCUCAGCGACCAGGAA